ACCCCGCUGUGACGCGCACGCUGUAGGAAAACUAAUUAAUUAAAAGGAUUUACGGUAUAUCUUAUGACUCUACAGGAGCCUUGGGAUAUAGUUACAGUAGCCAUCUUAGUUGGAAACUACUUUGGAAACCACGUGGAAGAUGGCAGGGCCAGCCUGGGUCCACAGAUGAUCUUGUGAAACACACCUUCCCCUGUCACCCCAUAUUUUGGCAUGAAAAAGAAGAAUUUCUUUCUCACUUGAGCUACUUUUGAGUCUCUUUGUUAUGGCAGAAAGUUUAUACGCUAAUAUAAAAUGGAAAGCAUUUCAGAGUUUUAAGUUUUUCUUUAUACUGUUUGCUAUAUUGUCUAUAUAUUGGUAUGGUAUUCUCAAUUAAAGUAGUUUUUAAAAUACAUAUGAUUACAUGCCAAGAGUUCCUUUUUGAUUAAUUAUUUGAGAGAAUGUUUUGCAAAUUUCCAAGUUACUUUUAAGCUUUUGGUAUUAAUAAUAGAAUGAUGUUAAUAUAUGGCAUUCUGCUUUUCUAGAUUUUUAUGGUUGUAUUUCUGGACUAGCCUAUGAUCAGUUUUCGUAAAGUUACACAGACCUUUUUAAAGAAGUUUUCUUUAUGAGAUACCUAAAUACCUAUUAUGUUGUUGAACUUUAUUAUUUUUUUGUCUGAUCUCUCAAAGGCUUAAAGUUGUAAAUCACUGAUUUCUUCCGUCAAUUUUAAUUAUUUGUAGUUCUAUAAGUUUUUAUUUUGGUGUAUGUGUUAAUGUGUUAUGUGUUAUUUACUGUCAGCAUCUCAAUUGAGGAUUAUACCUUUUAUCAGAGUAAUAUGACUUCUUUUUUUUUUUUUUAUUAAAUAAAGGGUCUUGCUUUGUCACCAAGGCUGGAAUGCAGAGGCACGAUCAUAGCUCAUUGCACCUUCCAAUCUCUAGGGCUCAAGUGGGCAAUCCUCCUGGCUAGCUGGUACUAUAAGUGUGCCACUACACCUGGCUAAUUUUUCCUUUUAAUUUUUUGUAGAGAUAGGGCCUUGCUAUAUUGCCCAGACUGGUCUUGAACUUCUGGCCUCAAGCGAUCCUUCUGGCCUAGCCUCCCAAAGUGCUGGGAUUACAGGUGUGUGCCACUGCACCCAGCCAUGACUUUCUAAUUUAUGACUUGUGUUUUGUUUUAGCUGACAUUGAUAUUGCUACCUUAGUUUAUAUUUCUCCAUAAAUCUGUGCUUCCCGUUAUAUUUACACUUUCUUUGUCAUUACUUUUAGAUAUGUUUCCUAAAAGUAGAACAUACUUGGAUUUUAUUUUUUAUCCUAAAAAGAACUUUGUCUCUUAACAAAUAUUUAAUGCAUUUAAAUUUGUUUCCAAAUUGUUCUGAUUGGUUUUAUUGAUCUUUUCAGCUUUUUGUUUGAAAUUCUUCCUUGUUUUCAUUGUGUUUUGGAUUUUUUGCUGUUUUGAUUUAAAGUUUUAUGUUUAAUUUGGUUUUCAUUUUUAACUUAUUGUGCAUCUAAGGCUUUGAAAACUAAGGAUUAUUUUAAAUAUUUUUUUAACUUUAAAUUUAUAUGACACCUAUCAUUAACAGUUAAGAAUAGGAUGGUAUCUCUUGAUAAAUGAGAAAUUUAAUAUGUUUUUACUUAUCUGCUUCUCUGUUUUCAUUAAUAUGAUCUAAGAUUUUUAACUCAAGACUGUUACUAAAUUAUAAUUUUAAAUAAUUUAUGCACAAUUUAUUUUAUUAACUUUUAUAUGGGCAUAAAGAAUAUGAAAACCCUAAGUUGUCACAACCUUAAUUUCUACUUUUUCAAGUAUUUAUCAAAAGGAAUCUUAAACCAUCAAAAUUAUAUUCUGAUAUCCUAUUACUUAUUAUUUUGAUUUAUUUUCAUAUUAUAUCUUUAAAAAAUACUGUUUUCAUUUUUUCUGUUGCCCACAUUCGAACUAUUUCUUUGCUCAUUAGACUAGGAGAAAAGAAGUAGAAAUAGUCAGAUGUGAAAUUAAGAUACCAAAUUAUGUAUUUGGUAUUUUCUGUAGCAAAGUCUAAGGUCUGGAACAUGUUUAGGAUUAUUGGAUUAAUGGAUUUUAUGGUGAUGGGUUUUAUGGGGAGAAUUACCAGUUAUUUAGUAGCUUGUAAGCUUGUGUCCUAAGAUGUCCCUGUCAAUUACUGCAUCAGGUAACACAGGGCGUGGCACUUAGAUUCUCAUUGGUAUUUGUUCAGUGACAGAAGCUGUCCUCUAUUGCUUUCGAGUCUCUAAGACUGUUUUCCCCAUCUUGAAUGUGCCUAGUCAUCUGACCUCCUCUCAAAUGGGCACCAACUUCAUUCUCUCUGUAUAAUAAGGGACCUUGUAUGGGGCUUUCCUAGUUUUUUUCAGAACAUGCUUGAGGACCAUUUAGGGAAGCAGGGUCUUAGAGGACAUUCAGUCUUGUCUUGGAAACAGUGGGGAAGGAAGAACUCUGUAGCAGUUGCUAGGGGUAAUAUUAUAUCUUUAAGAAAACAAUGCUGUCACUAAGUUACUUUUAGACAUGGAAGGCUUCUCUUUAAUUUUUUUUUCUUUUUUAGUGGAUGAUUAUGUAGCUAGACUACCAAGAGGUAGGGAGUGAAGUAAAGCUGAGAACAGCCUCUCCAGGAUUAUCAGGUUAGGGUGAAGUUCUUGGCAAGAGACUGGAUUUAGUGUGGUAUUCUGGAAAGCACAUGGGCUGAGGAGGCAGGAGACCUUUAUUCUAAUUUUGGUUCUCUGUUCUUGUUUCUAACUGUGGCAAACCAUUUAACUUUUGUGAGUCUCAGACUAGAUUUAUUAAAUGAGGAAUCUGACUCAAAGAUCCUUUCUAACUUUAAAAUUCUGUGUCUGACCAGAGGACCAGGGUAGAACAAGGAGGUUUCUACUCAAUAGCAUUUUUAUUUUUAAUUUCAUUUUGUAAAGUCAAGAGGAAUAAACCAUUUAUCUUACUGCUUUGAACAGGAGGAUUAGAAGAAGGAAUCAUAUAUGGCUCACAUGUUUAUGUUCUGACUUCGUAUUAGGAAAAUACUAAUGUCCGUCAGUCAACAAAUACUUGCAGAAUGCUAGUGUAAACAGCAUUGUGCCUGGUAUUGUGGACUCUCCAGAGAUGUGCAUCACCUUGUUCCUGCCAUCUGAAGUGUCCUAGACUUCUCAACGAAGAGGAUAUGGACACUAAUCAAGUUAAACAGCAACCUAAAAUGGAGUUUCACUCUUGUCGCCCAGGCUGGAGUGCAGUAUCACGAUCUCGGCUCACUUCAACUUCCACCUCCUGGGUUCAAGCAAUUCUCCUGCCUCAGCCUCCUGAGUAGCUGGGAUUACAGAUGCCCGCCACCAUGCCCAGCUAAUUUUUGUAUUUUUGGUAGAGACAGGGUUUCACUCUGUUGGCCAGGCUGGUCUCAAACUCCUGACUUCAGGUGAUCUGCCCACCUUGGCCUCCCAAAGUGCUUACAGGUGUGAGCCACUGUGCCCGGCCAACCUCUUAAAGUUUCUUUCACAAUAAAGCAUGUACUAAUAUUACAAACUAUUUUAGUCCUAUUUUUUGUUUUGUAAAGGAGAUUUUAAAAUGAAUAUAAUUUAUAUUGAGACCCUUUGAUUAUAUUUACUUAUUAAAAGCAAACCCAUUAGUGCAUUUUAGAGUCAAACAUCUACUUGUAUUAUUUUAUUAUAUAGCUAAAGGAAAAAUAAUGCCACACAGAAACGAAACCAGUUUUUCCAAAACAGUAAAGAUGGAAUCUUGAGACAGUCUGCUCACUUUAAUUUUUAUUUUAUAUUUUAGUCUUCUGGCCAGUAGCAAAUUGAUGUGACCUUGUGCAUGUUUCUCUGAAUAUCCACAGUUGUUCAGCUGUAUGAAUUGCUGCCAGUGUGACAAUGAGCCGGAAGCUAUAUCCAACUUGCUUCUCACACUGUAUUUUUGUAAAGACCUAGAUUCUUUCAAGAUAUUACUAAGUGAUCCGUGAUUAAAGGUUUUGGUGGUUUGCUAAUUUUAGGAAAAGUGGGAGCAAUCACAAUGUAUAUUACGUAGUGUAUAUUGGUAUUUUAUUUAACCCAGUGUUUCCCAAAUGUAUUUGAACUUGGGAACACCCACCCCCUGUCUUUCUUCCUUCCAAAUUCCUUCCUUUCUUACUUUAUUUUUAAAGAACACUUACUAAAAUCUCUUAUAGAACAAGUUUCAGGAAUGUGCACUAUGAAACUUUCAUACACACAUGCACGUUAUUUAGAUGUGUUGCUUAUGUCUUUUUCUAUUAAUCUCCAACUUUUCUGGGGCAUAGGUUGGGAGGAAGAAGGAAAGUGAGUAACUUACAAGUUUUACUAGUUAUUCUGAUGUCAAGUUUAGUGGGAAAGAGGCUGAAGCUUAUAUCUAAAAUAAGGUUUGAGAUUGAUCUGAGUAUUUUAAGAGUUCUUACUAUCUGUAUCUUCUAUAGUUUGUUGCUCUGUACAAGCAGGAGUUGACAGAGCAUAACAGAAGUUACCUUUAUGGGAAAGAGUAAGGUGGGUUGGAGGUGAAAUAAGACUUUUCGCUUUUGUAACCUUAAGAAGAAAAAGCAAAUUAAAAGACCUAAACUGAUGGAGAGAACCAGUACUUUACAACAGAAUUUCUUAUUUCAAGCUUUUGUAAGUACUAGCCUCUCUGGUAGUUUUAAACGCAUUUUGUUUAGAAAGUACCAAAAUUUGUAAAACUUUUUUUUUUUUUUUUUCUUUUGGGAUGGAGUCUCACUCUGUCACCCAGGCUGGAGAGCAGUGGUGCAAUCUCGGCCCACUGCAACCUCCACCUCCCGGGUUCAAGCGAUUCUGCUGCCUCAGCCUCCUGAGUAGCUAGGAUCACAGGCGCACGCCACCACACCCGGCCAAUCUCUUGUAUUUUUAAUAGAGACGGGGUUUCACCAUGUUGGCCAGGCUGGUCUCGAACUCCUGAUCUCAAGUGAUUCACUCACCUUGGCUUCCCAAAGUGCUUGGAUUACAGGCGUGAGCCACUGUGCCCAGCCCUAUUCUUGUCUUCUAAUACAGGCAGGUUAGAAGGGAUUCUAUCAAAUUUAAAAUUUAGCACUUUUUGUUUAAAAAAAAUAAAAUGCGAUUAUACAAUCAAAGAACAUUAAAGCUGGUAGAAGUUUCACAAAUCAUUUGUUUCAGGCCAGGCACAGUUGUGCACACCUGUAGUCCCAGCUACUCAGGAGGCUGGGGCGGAAGGAUCGCCUGAGCCCAGGAGUUCAUGGCUAUAGUGCGCUAUGAUCAUGCCUGUGAAUAGCCGCUGUUCUCCAGCCUGGGCAACAUAGCGAGACCUCAUUUCUAAUAAUUUUUUAAAAAGGUAUAAUAAAUUAAAAAAUUUUUUUUUUUAAUUUUUUUUUUUUAUUUAUUAUACUCUAAGUUUUAGGGUACAUGUGCGCAUUGUGCAGGUUAGUUACAUAUGUAUACAUAUGUAAAAAAAACUUUUUUUUUUUUUAAGAAACAGGCUUAUAUAAAGUAAGAUAAAUCUGGUAAGAUAAGAUUAAUAUCUUUUGUUCUUUAUCUUGUACAUACCUGUUAUUAAUAUACUAUGCCAUCAUUGUCUAUUUAAGUGCUAAGUGAGUAAGUAUAUAUUAUUUUUCUCUGUAUCUUUGGCACCUAACCUUGCACUGUGCCUGGUACAUAGUAGGCAUUCAGUAAAUGUUUGUUGAUGUGAGUGUCGGGGGUGGGAAAACUUAAUUUUACAGUCAAUCCUAGGGGAAUACGUUAAUGGUUGAAAUCUUAAAAGGAUUAUGUUAUUUUGAAAACGUCUUUAAAAUAUAGCCUAUUUUAUUUUUAUAUUUAUAUCUAUCUUGUCUAAGAAAGGAUUUAAGGUGGUAUUACUAAGUACACUUAGUACAGUGGGAUCAAAUAAAAUUUAAAAUAAAUGAGUAAAAGAACAAAAUUGGAGGAUUUAUACAUCCCCAUUUCAAAACUCAAUCUAAGGUGACAGUAUUCAGGACAACGUGGCCGUGGCAUAGGAUAAGCAUAUAAAUCAAUGGAGAGGAAUUGAGAGUCCAGAAAUAAACAUUUACAUUUUUGGUCCAUUGAUUUUUGGAAGAGCUGCUAAGACAAAUAGAGAAAGGGUUAUUUUUUCAACAAAUGGUGCUGGAAAAAUUGGAUAUCAUAUACAAAAAUUAACUUCCUCACAAUAACAAUACACAAAAAUUAGCUGACAAUGAAUUAGGGGCCUAAAUGUAAGAGCUAAAAUUAUAAAACUUCUAAAAGAAAGCAUAGAAGAAACUUUAUGACCUUGGAUUAGGCAGAGUUGUUAGGUAUGACACCAGAAGCAUGAGCCAUAAGAUAAAAAAUUGAUGAAUUUGACUUAAUUAAAAUUAACAUUUUUAUGCUACAAAAGACAUUGGGAAGAAACUGAAAAGAUAGGCUGCAGACUGGGAGAAAAUAUUUGCAAAUCAUGUGUGAUAAAGGACUUGUAUCCAAAACAUGUAAAGAAUUAUAAGUAAAUAAUAAGGCAAACAACCCAACUUAACAGUGAGCAAAAGAACAGAAUAGACACUUCAUCUGAAAAGACAUGAGAGUGAUUAAUAGCCACAUGUAAGCACAGUGAGCAUCAUUAGUCAUUAGGAAGAUACACAUUAAAAACACAAUGAGAUACCACAAUGAGAUUACAUCCCCUAGGAUGGCUGUAAUAAAAAAGACAGUAUAUAGUGUCUAGGAUGUGGAGAAACAGGAACUCUCAUAUUAUACAUUGUUGGUAGGAAUGUAAAUUGUUAUAACCACUUUGGAAAAUAGUUUGGCUAUUUCUUUUAAAGUUAAACCAACUUACCAUAUGUAGUAAGGUUCUCCAGAGAGACAGAAUGAAUCAGGUAUGUGUGUGUGUGUGAAGAAAUUUAUUUAUUGAGACGGAGUCUGGCUCUGUCACCCAGGCUGGAGUGCAGUGGUGCGAUCUCGGCUCAUUACAAGCUCCGCCUCCCGGGUUCACGCCAUUCUCCUGCCUCAGCCUCCUGAGUAGCUGGGACUACAGGCACCUGCCAACACGCCCGGCUAAUUUUUUUUUUUUUUUUGUAUUUUUAGUAGAGACGGGGUUUCACCGUGUUAGCCAGGAUGGUCUCAAUCUCCUGACCUCGUGAUCCGCCCACCUCGGCCUUCCAAAGUGCUGGGAUUACAGGUGUGAGCCACCGCGCCCGGCCAAAAUUUAUUUUAAGGAAUUAAUUGGCUCAGAAAGAGUUGCAGUUUGAGUCUAAAGGCAGUCAGCUGGAAAACCAGAAGAGCCAAUGUUGCAGAUGAAGUCUGAAGGGAGUCUGCUGGGGACUUCCCUUUUGCCCAGGGAGGUCAUCCUUUUGUUCUAUUCAGGCCAUCAACUCAUUAGAUGAAGCUCCCCCAUAUAAUGGAGAACCAUCUGCUCUACUCAAAGUCUAACAGUCUAAAUGCAGAUCUUGUCCAAAAUUACUCUUGCAGAAAUGUCGAGAAUAAUGUUUGACCAAAUAUCUGAGUGCUGUGGUCCAGCCAAACUGAUACAUAAUUUUUAAUCAUUGUGCCAUAUAAACUCAGCAAUUCCACUUCUUGGAAUCUGCCCAAGAGAAAUGAAAACAUAUGUUCACACAAAGACUUGUAUGUAAUUGCUCUUGGCAACAUUAUUUGUAAUAGAUAUUAAUAAAAACAAGAAAAAAUGCAAUGUCCAUAACCUGGUAAAUGGAUAAACAAAAUGAGGCAUAUCUAUACAUUGGAAUACUAUUCAGCAAUGAAAAAGGAAGAAAAUAUUGAUAUAUGCUGCAGCAUGGAUGAAACUAAAAAAUAUAGUGUUGAGUGAAAGGAACUAGACUCAAUAGACUACAUAUUAUAUGAUUUCACUUAUGAAAUUUCUAGAAAAGGGAAACUGAUUGAGUUAGCAAGGAGAUUAGAGGGGAACUAGGGGUUGGAGCAGGAAUUGACUGCAUAUGAACUCAAGGGAAUUGGGAGAGAUAAUGGAAAACUGGAUUGUAGUGAUGAUUGCAUCCAUUUAGUACAUUCUGGUCCUCUAUAAAUGGACUAAAACGUCAUUGAACUGUCCCCUGUUCAAUGGACAAUGAUUAAUUUUAUGGCAUAUAAAUUGCACUUCAAUCCAUAUCAAAAUUAUAAAAGUAGUACAAAUGGAGUAAGGAUGGGACACACAUUAUAUCUUAUAAAAGCUCCUAUAUUUUGCUUGAGGUGGAUCAUGGAUUUUGCUCUAAGCUCUCUAAGAAGACAUCUCUCAAUAUGAAAUUUCUUUUCUGUUGUUCACAAGAUCAAAAUUUAUCAAUAUUUUAGGAGAAGCCUAAUAAUUAUAUUCAAAGGAAAAUGUAUUCUUUUUGUUAUAGUGCAGUGUAAUCAAGUCUGUCCUUAAAUAACAUCCUCAUAGUAAAUAACUGAAGACUCUCUUCUGAAGACCUGUUUCUUGAGCCCCCUUUCUAUACAGUCUGGUAGCCUAACAUCAAAGGCACAUUGAUAAAUACAGCCCUGUUGAGUGAAUAGGGAGGAGAUCAGCAAAAGUACAAGGCCAGGAAUGCUAUUCUUUGGUCGUAUGACUCAGUCCCAAAAAUGGAACUACAAAAGACCUCGAGUAGCCAAAGCAACAUUGGGAAAAAGAACAAAGCUGGAGGCAUCACACUACCUGACUUCAAAUUAUACUACAAAGCAUUUCCAAACCUCAAGAAAAAUAUAAAUAUCCAGGCACAGGAAGGUCAAAGGUCAUACAGCCUACCAAGACCAAAUCAUAAUGGAAUAGAACACCUGAGUACAGCAAUAAUGAGUCACAAAAUUGAAUCAGUAAUAAGAAUUAGUCCAUCAAAGAACAGCCCAAACCCUGAUGCUUUUCCUGUUGAACAUUUAAAAUAGUAAUAAUGUCAAUUCUCCUCAAAAUAUCCCAAAGAAUAUUAACCAAUAGUAACCAAAACAGCAUGGUACACACAUAAAAACAGACACAUAGGACAGUGGUACAGAAUAGAGAACCCAGAAAUCCAUGUAUUUACAGCCAGCUGAUUGAUGAACAUGCUAAGAGCACACAUUGGGGAAAGGACAUCCUCUGAAAUAAAUGGGGCUAGGAAAACUGGACAUCCAUGUGCAGAAACUAGAUACCUGUUUCUUACCAACAUCAACUCAAAAUGGAUUAAAGACAGACUAUGAAACUAUUAGAAUACACAGGAGAAACACUUCAUGACAUUGGUCUAGAUAAGGUUUGUAUGGGUAAGACUUCAAAAGCACAGACAAGGAAAGAAAAAAUAAACAAAUGGGAUUACAUCAAACUUAAAGCUCUAUACAGCAAAGGAAACAACAGAGUGAAGAGACAAUCUGUAGAAUGGGAGAAAAUAUUAGCUAACUACACAUCUGACAAGGGGUUAACAUCCAGAAUGUGUAAGGAAUCUGAACAACUCAAUAGCAAAAAGCAAGCAAACAAUCUGAAUGCUAAAGUGGGAAAAGAUCUGAAUAGAUAUUUCUCAAAAGAAGACAUGCAAAUGGCAACAGACAUAUGAAAAAAUGUUCAACAUCACUACAUCAGGGAAACGCAAAUCAAAACAGUAAUGAGAUUAUCAUCUUACCCCAGUUAGAAUGGCUAUUACCAAAAAGACAAUAACAAGUCCUGGCAAGGAUGUGGAGAAAAGGGAACUGUUAAUUUACACUGUUGGUGGGAAUGUAAAUUAGUACAGCCAUAAUAAAAAACAGCAUGGAAGUUCUUUAAAAUAUUAAUAACAGAACUACCAUAUGAUCUAACAGUUUCACUGUACGGCUUAUAUAUCCAAAAUAAGUGAAAUCAGUAUGUUGUUGAAGAGAUACCUGCCCUCCUAUGUUUAUUGCAGCACUAGUUACAAUAGCCAAGAUAUGGAAUCAACCUAAGUGUUUAUUAGUGUAUGAAUGGAUAAAUAAAAUAUGUCAUAUAUACACAAUGGAAUACUAUUCAGCCAUAGAAAAGAAUGAAAUUCUAUCAUUUGCAGUGAACAUGGAUGAACCCAGAGGUCAUUAUAUUAAGUGAAAUAAGCCAGGCAUCUCAUUUAUAUGUGGAAUCUAAAAACGUUUAUCUCAUAGAAGUAGAAAGUAGAAUAGUGGUUACCACUGGGUGGGGAAGAGAUAGGAGAGAUGAAGAGAGGUUGGUCAACAAGUGCAAACCUACAGUCACAUAGGAGGAAUAAGUUCUGGUGUUCUAUGGUACAGUAGGGUGACUUUAGUUAAUAAUAACAUAUUUCAAAAUACAAGAGAAGCUUUGAAUGUUCUCAUUAAAAAAUGACAAGUAUCAGAAUACCACACUGUAUUCCAUAAAUAUAUACAAUUAUUAUGUGUCAAAAAUAAAAUAAAACUUUAAAAAGAUGUCAGUUUGGUCACACACAUAUUUACGUAAACAUAGUUUAUCAUUUCACUAACAGUCUCUCUUUUAUAUUUCAUCACUUAUCUCACAUUGGUAUUUUUUAUGUUGUGUUUGAAAAUCACUGCUGUAGAGUACCAUAAAGGGUCUUAAUUUUCUAUUUGUAAUCCCACUCUUGCUUCAAUCAUGAGAAAGUGACUGAAUAACUGUGUUAAAUGAACUGAAGGAGAGCCUGAGCAUGAAUCCUUUGGCUUGAUUAUCUAUGUACAAUAGUUUAUUUAGUAAGACGAAAAUGGUUAUAAUUGCAGUGAUUUAGUUGGAGUAUAUUGUGUUUGAAAAAUUGUUUGUUUUAGAAUAUCUUAGAGAAAAUUGGCCUCUCAGAAAUAAUUUUACCUUAUAAUGAACUUUGCAAAUUGCUUCUGCAAAAUCACUAGGUUCAGGUUUCUGCUUUCAGUUAGGUUGUAGAAGGUGGUAAUGGGACAUUGUGGCUUCUGGAACAACUAAAAAAAAUAAUAAUAAGUUACAAAAAUCAACGUUGUAAUAAUAUGUUACUACCUAAUAAAAUGCCCCAAUAUUCAGUGGUGUGAAACAGCAAGUCUCAUUUAGCUCAUCGUUCUAUGGGUUGAAAAUUCAGGCAGGUCCCAGCUUGGUGAUUUUUGGUUGCAUGUUUCGUUGACUGAGAUCACUGGGUGGUAUUCUGCUGGUGGAUGGAAUUCUCUGGAGGAUUCAAGAUACAUAUAUACAGGGUGCCUGGGCAGAGGUGGAAGGCUAAGUCUACAUGACCUUUCUAGCAUGGUAGUCUUAGCAUAGUCAGACUUAUUAUUGUGGCUUCCGGCUUCUAGAGAGAAUUUUCGUGGAGAUAGAAAGUGGACGCUGCCAGCGUCUUAAAGCCUAAAACUGAAAAAUGGUACCAUAUCACUUCCACUAUAUUCUGUUGGUCAAAGGAGUCACAGAGUUCUUCCAGUUUUAGUGAGAGAAGACAUAGGCAUGACCUUCCAGUGGAAGAAGUAUCAAAACAUUUGUGGCCAUCUUUAAUCCACCACAGUCCACUAUCUGGUCACAAAUGAUUCAGUCUCUUCCUAUGUUCCUUAUUUACUCACCCACCUCCAAGAAUCCCAAAAUUAUUUUCCAACUCUUCUUUACCCUGAGUCUUAAAGUUCAAGAACUUGUUAUUUACAACAAGUACACUGUUCAGGAAUCUUCUCAGGUGUAGCUGAAGAGACAACUACCCAACAAUAUAAUGAAGAGGCAGUCAUAGAAUAGCUGCAGUAAACAUUCCCAUUCACAAAUAGGGAAACAGGAAACAUACAGCUUUACUGGUCCAUAGAAAUUUUGAUAUACUGAUGUUAGUUCUUUUAUUAGGCUAUUCUUGCCUCCUGAUAAUGAUUCUCCCUGGCUCGAGGUUUUGCUCUCUCAAUUUAGAGUCAUCCUUUUUCUGUAAGAAAUGGUCAUUUUUUGCAACUGAGUAGCCUUUUCAGCCUUUCUGCCUGUAGAAAUUUGAGAGUCCAAAAGCCUGUUUUCAUUUUGCACUAUCUCUGUCCCUUUCAGUGCAAGCUGAUAUAAUGUUUUUUAAAACUUUGUGGGCUUCCUGUGUAUCAAAUUGUAGCCCGCUCCAUUAAUCAGAGGCCCACCCACAUUUAUUUUAGAGAGGCAUUUUUUUUCUUUCAUACUGAGUCAAGGUAUUUUGAAACAACACCCAUAAUAUUCCUAUGAGCUUUUCUGUCUAUUUAAGAGUCCAAAGUGCACAUCAUCAAGAUUCUUAGAGGCCUUUUGCCUUAGAACAGAAUCUAAGUGUCAUACUCUUAAGAUUCUUAGAACUGAACUAGAUACGAUUUUAGUCUUUCAGUCUCAACAAGGUGUUUUACAGCCAUGCUGUAGAGAUUUUUAUCCUGAAACCACGCUUUACUGAUAAAAAUGAAUGCCAUUUCCCAUCCAGUACUGAAGUGUUAAAGUUAGAAGACAUUUGCUAAGUCAAAUCACUUCAGGUAUGUUGAAGAAAGUACGCACAUCUUAUCUUCUGAACAUUUUGAUGGAAUUAACCACAAACUUCAUGCAAGAACAGUAAAAGGAAAGAUACUAUUCAAGUCCAGUACAUCAUAAUGCAGAAUUCUGUAUCAGUACCACCAAAAGAUGAAGGUGAAUCAAACAUCCCUUCUGGAACAAUACAGAGUAGGAAAGGUUUGCAGAAUAAGAGUCAGUUUAGGACCAUUGCACCAAAAAUUGUGCCCAAAGUCCUAACGUCCAGAAUGCUGCCAUGUCAUUCACCAUCACGCUCUGAUCAGGUGAAUCUGGGACCCUCCAUCAACUCCAAGCUGCUGGGGAUGUCCACCCAGAACUAUGCCCUGAUGCAGGUUGCUGGCCAGGAGGGGACAUUUUCUCUUGUUGCUCUGCCACAUGUUGCCUCAGCUCAGCCAAUUCAGAAACCCAGAAUGUCCCUACCUGAAAACCUGAAACUUCCUAUUCCUAGAUAUCAACCCCCUAGAAAUAGCAAAGCAUCAAGAAAGAAACCCAUCCUGAUCUUUCCUAAGAGUGGCUGUAGCAAAGCUCCUGCCCAAACCCAAAUGUGUCCUCAGAUGUCCCCUUCCCCACCUCACCACCCUGAACUCCUGUACAAACCCAGUCCAUUUGAGGAAGUACCAUCACUAGAGCAAGCCCCAGCCAGCAUUAGCACAGCUGCGCUGACCAAUGGAAGUGACCAUGGGGACUUGAGACCACCAGUGACCAACACCCAUGGCAGUCUGAACCCUCCUGCUACCCCAGCAUCAUCCACACCAGAGGAGCCUGCCAAGCAGGACCUCACAGCUCUUUCAGGGAAAGCACACUUUGUAAGCAAGAUAACAUCUAGUAAACCUUCUGCUGUUGCCAGUGAAAAAUUUAAAGAACAAGUUGAUCUUGCAAAAACCAUGACCAAUUUAUCACCAACCAUUCUUGGCAAUGCAGUUCAGUUGAUCUCUUCAGUCCCCAAAGGGAAACUGCCAAUCCCACCCUACUCAAGAAUGAAGACAAUGGAGGUUUACAAAAUCAAAUCAGAUGCUAACAUUGCAGGUUUUUCUUUACCAGGACCUAAGGCCGACUGUGAUAAGAUACCCUCCACCACAGAAGGCUUUAAUGCAGCCACCAAGGUGGCAAGCAGGCUACCUGUUCCACAAGUGUCACAGCAGAGUGCCUGUGAAAGUGCCUUUUGUCCACCCACCAAACUUGAUCUUAACCACAAAACAAAACUGAACAGUGGAGCAGCAAAGAGAAAAGGAAGAAAACGGAAGGUACCAGAUGAAAUUUUGGCAUUUCAGGGAAAAAGGAGGAAAUAUAUCAUUAAUAAGUGUAGAGAUGGUAAAGAAAGAGUAAAAAAUGAUCCCCAAGAAUUCAGAGACCAAAAGCUGGGGACCCUGAAAAAAUACCGUAGCAUUAUGCCCAAACCUAUCAUGGUCAUACCCACUUUGGCCUCCCUGGCUUCUCCAACUACACUACAGUCCCAGAUGCUUGGGGGCCUAGGACAGGAUGUUUUGUUAAAUAAUUCACUCACUCCUAAAUAUCUUGGCUGUAAGCAAGACAACAGCUCUUCCCCUAAGCCCAGCUCCGUGUUCAGAAAUGGAUUCUCUGGCAUUAAGAAGCCUUGGCACAGAUGUCACGUCUGCAACCACCACUUCCAGUUCAAACAGCACCUUCGAGACCACAUGAAUACACACACCAACAGACGCCCUUACAGUUGUCGGAUUUGUCGCAAGUCCUAUGUACGUCCUGGCAGCCUGAGCACACACAUGAAACUUCAUCAUGGUGAGAACCGUCUGAAGAAACUCAUGUGUUGUGAGUUUUGUGCAAAAGUGUUUGGCCACAUCCGAGUCUAUUUUGGCCAUCUGAAAGAAGUGCAUAGGGUUGUGAUCAGCACUGAGCCUGCGCCCAGUGAACUGCAGCCAGGAGACAUACCAAAGAACAGAGACAUGAGUGUGCGAGGCAUGGAGGGAUCAUUGGAGAGGGAAAACAAGUCCAACCUGGAAGAAGACUUCCUUCUAAACCAGGCAGACGAAGUCAAAUUACAAAUCAAAUGUGGUCGUUGUCAGAUUACUGCUCAGUCUUUUGCGGAAAUAAAAUUUCAUUUACUUGAUGUUCAUGGAGAGGAAAUUGAGGGCAGGCUACAAGAAGGGACCUUCCCAGGAAGCAAGGGGACUCAGGAAGAGUUGGUGCAGCACGCUAGCCCCGACUGGAAAAGGCAUCCUGAGAGAGGGAAGCCGGAGAAGGUUCAUUCCUCCUCCGAGGAAUCACAUGCAUGUCCAAGACUGAAAAGGCAGCUCCACCUUCAUCAGAAUGGCGUGGAAAUGCUCAUGGAAAAUGAAGGACCCCAGUCAGGAACCAACAAGCCAAGGGAAACCUGCCAGGGCCCUGAGUGUCCUGGCCUCCACACGUUUCUCUUGUGGUCCCAUUCAGGCUUUAACUGCCUGCUUUGUGCAGAGAUGCUGGGACGGAAAGAGGACCUCCUCCACCACUGGAAGCACCAGCAUAACUGUGAGGACCCUUCCAAACUGUGGGCUAUUUUAAAUACGGUCUCCAACCAGGGAGUGAUCGAACUUUCCAGUGAAGCUGAGAAAUGAGACCCCAAGGCAGCCUGGGGUUAAGGAGAGAGCUCUGCCGCCACCUUCCUUCAGAGCUUCGUGCUUUAUGGUGGUGCUUAGUCACAAAGAUCAAACAACAGGAUUGGUGUGAGUGAACAGAAAUGAUUUUUGUACAUGGUUUUAUUUUCUUAACGAAAUAAAAUAUAAGCUCUCGAAGCAUAUUUUUCUAACUAUAUGCAGUCUUAUUUUAAAAUACGUACUGAUUCUUAAUAUCUUAGACUUUCAGAAUAAAUAAAAAGAUCAAAAUUUGAAGAUUGAAAUUUAGCAGAAUAUAGGCUGUUCUUCAAAUACAGCUCUCAGUGAAAACA